GUCCCGAUCCCGGCGUGGCUUUCCCCAGUCCACGAAGUCUUCUACGGACAUAUCCUCCUGUUCCCCAAGAGGAUGGCACAGGGAGAGUUCUGAGUGGUCUCGGGCAAUGGCUGCAUUUGCUGUUGGCCUGUAAGCAGGCCAGAAGCAGAGGAAGAGAGAGAAGGUAAAACCCGCCCAUGGACCGCAAGCGUGAGAGCCAAGGCAGGACUAUGAACUGUCAAAAUUGUCUCUGACUUCUCACCAGGCCGGAGAGGAGGGAUCUAGUGCGUGAGGCACUACUUGGUUUGGGACAAGUCAGAGGCGAAUAAAAGCUCUUCCUGCCUUGAAGAAGCUUACAGUUUUGUGGGAAAAUGAUCUGCAAUGGGAAUACAUACGAUAUGACAAAUGUUCUAUUAUGAAAAUGCAUGCCUGUAUUCAACUUAGAACAUCAAAGUAAUCUCAGAUACUAACAAGAAUGUCCAACGAAUCUCUACAUAAGUGCAGGCUUUUUUUUUUUUUUUUUUUUUUAAUGAGAAGGAUUGAAAAUACUAUCCCGUGACAGGUCAACCUUGUCUUGGAAAUCUCAGAAAUCUCAAUCUUAUCCAUAGAAAAGUCAUGACUUCUGUGCUUAUGUCCAUUUGUUCUUUAAAUACCAAACUGUCAGCUCAUAGGAACCAUUUACACACACACACUGACACACACACAAACACGCACACCCCUACUUACUGAGAUGUUCCUGGGGAGAUUCGAAGACCUGUUCCAUUGAGAAAACAAGAAUAAGCCCCUGGGGCAAAAGACUCCGCGUCUCUGGGGAACUCAGUAUCCGCGCCGCGAGCACCCAUGCCCAUUUUGAACACAACGCGACUGCUAAGGACGUGGUGUAAUCAUAUGGACCUUCACUCCCAAGAGACUCGAUUUCAGAGAAAAUCUGGGAGACAAAUUUAGAUCCCUACCCGCACCCACGCGAUCAAUAAAGCUGGGGAGACCUUUGGGGGAGGGGACAGAUGUGCUUGCAUCCGGGCCGUGCGUGCCUGCUUCACGGGUUUUCCGGGCAGCACCGGCCCGCACACGCCGGUGCACUCUUUUUCUGGAAUUCUUGAAAUAGCCGGGCCUGAGGACAGUAAGGGAGCUGAGUUGUGUCUGCUACAGACAAGCGGCGCAGAGCCUGGGGGCCAAGCCAGGGAUGCAGGGAGCGCGGCGUUAGCGGAUGACGGAUAGCUCAGGGCUAAGGCCUGGCAGGUCCUUCCUACCCCCGACCCAGUACACCCCGCAGCCCCGCCCUCGCCCCAGCACGCGAGGUGAAAGCGCGAGGCCCGGGGAUGGCGGAGAGCGUGCGCCACUAUCGGGGCGCUGUCUCUUGCCCCGCUCUCGCCCUGGGCCGGAGAACGGAGAAGGUCCGCAGGCCUCGGGCCACGGAGGGCACCAGAUCGGUCCGCUCUGCUCCGCUAACCCAGCCUGCGCCCCUCCACCCCGCCAAGGCCCUGCUGGGCGCUGCGCCGGUUGCUCGCGUCCUCUGUUGUCGCGGAGCCGCCGCCGCCGCCGCCCGCGAACCAGCAACGCCGACACCCAGCAGUUGCAGGCCCGGCGUUUGCCGCCGCGGUUUUUCCACCCAGCACUGAGGAUCAAGCCCGCUGUAGCCUGGCUGCGACUCCCCGCUUGGGAGCAGAGGCCGCCAGGGGCCUCCAGGCCGAGAGAUUCUGGAGCCUUUCCAGGGCGCGGCGGGGAGCGGGGCCUCCGGAAACCCACCCCGGGGAUGCUGGAGUCUGUCCUGCAGAGGCCGUGGCGCGGGCACUGCUGCCUGAUUUCGAAGAGGCUCCAUCAACCUACUCUCUUCCAAAGGGCUGGGCAGCCCAGCCACAGACAGGCAGCCUCUGGAUCUCAGAAGUGAGGGACGGAGUCUAUCCUGGGUUUGGUCCAGUAGAAACCCCCCACCCCCACCCCCAGAGUCUGGGAACCAGUGCUGUGCCCACAGAUGCAAAGAGAAAGAGCAUGGGUUAAAGCGCUAUUGGGAUCGGUUAGACACCACACUUUUCCAAGGAAGACAUUUUCUUCGAGAGGAACAGCAAAAGGAGUCAAUAUAAUGUUAAAAAUAUUAAGGCAGGUGCUGUGCCACAUGUUGAAGUGAUUCCAAAAGCAGAGAAAACAUGGGACUCACAUUUAAGAGGAUUAAUUGUAGCCUUUGAGUUUUUCCCAGAAAAAAAAAAAAGGCUAGCAUAUAUAUUUUCAUAUAUUUAUAUGAACAGGUAAUUAAAUAAGGAGGGAUUUUAAAAAAUUGUCUAUUUGGAUAUCGUUUUCCUUUCCAUUUGAGGAAAAGCCAAAUGCAAAUAAGGAGAAUAAUAUUUAAAGAACAUGCUUUUAAUAGAGCCUCAAUUAUCCUUCUAAUUUAACCAAGAUGAAAAUAAUUGUGAAAUAAAGCAAAAUAAAAUCUUGGAAGCAUAAA